UCUUCCUCCAGCUGUUCCCACAGGCUCCAUUAUUCAAACUUUGGGGGAGGAAAUCAGGGCUGGACAGAUCAUCAACUGCUGCUGCUGACAGACUGUGUUCCUGCCAUGAUGGGGACAGGCCUGCCCCAAACCAGGCUGUCUCACCAGAAACCAGCCCUAACACGCCAGAGCCCCAUCUCUCAGGUCGGCCUCCUGCCCUCCUCCCUCCCUCCCUCCCUCCCUCUCUCCUGCCUCAGCCCCGCCCCGGCCCCUGGGGCCCUCCCUGCUCCCGCUCCACUCCCCUCCCCGCCCCUCUGGACUGGCUGGGCAGGGCUGGGCCCCGCCGGUCGACAACACAGGGGCUGGGGCAGGCAGAUCAGAGGGAGCUGAGGGAGGCCUGACCUGAGGCCGGCACCCGGAGCUGGCGGGAGCCAGACCCAGAGCUCCCGCGGCCGCCCCUUCCCUGGGCCGGGUCAUGCGCUGCCCCAAGUGCCUUCUCUGCCUGUCAGCACUGCUCACACUCCUGGGCCUCAAAGUGUACAUCGAGUGGACAUCCGAGUCCCGGCUCAGCAAGGCCUACCCCAGCCCUCGGGGCACCCCGCCAAGCCCCACGCCAGCCAACCCUGAGCCCACCCUACCUGCCAACCUCUCCACCCGCCUGGGCCAGACUAUCCCGCUGCCCUUUGCUUACUGGAACCAGCAGCAGUGGCGGCUGGGGUCCCUGCCCAGUGGGGACAGCACUGAAACGGGGGGCUGCCAGGCUUGGGGGGCCGCCGCCGCCACCGAGAUCCCUGACUUCGCCUCCUACCCCAAGGACCUCCGCCGCUUCUUGCUGUCAGCAGCCUGCCGGAGCUUCCCACAGUGGCUGCCUGGAGGUGGUGGCAGCCAAGUCUCCAGCUGCUCAGAUACUGAUGUCCCCUACCUGCUGUUGGCCGUCAAGUCAGAACCAGGGCGCUUUGCAGAACGACAGGCCGUGAGAGAGACGUGGGGCAGUCCAGCUCCAGGGAUCCGGCUGCUCUUCCUGCUAGGGUCUCCGGUGGGUGAGGCGGGGCCUGACCUAGACUCACUAGUGGCCUGGGAGAGCCGUCGCUACAGUGACCUGCUGCUCUGGGACUUCCUCGACGUCCCAUUCAACCAGACGCUCAAAGACCUGCUGCUGCUGGCCUGGCUGGGCCGCCACUGCCCCACCGUGAGUUUUGUCUUGCGAGCUCAGGACGAUGCCUUUGUACACACCCCUGCCCUGCUGGCUCACCUGCGGGCCCUGCCACCUGCCUCGGCCCGAAGCCUCUACCUGGGUGAGGUCUUUACCCAGGCCAUGCCUCUCCGGAAGCCAGGAGGACCCUUCUAUGUGCCCGAGUCCUUCUUCGAAGGUGGCUACCCAGCCUAUGCAAGCGGGGGUGGCUACGUCAUUGCCGGGCGCCUGGCACCCUGGCUGCUGCGGGCGGCAGCCCGUGUGGCACCCUUCCCCUUUGAGGACGUCUACACUGGCCUUUGCAUCCGAGCCCUGGGCCUGGUGCCCCAGGCCCACCCAGGCUUCCUCACAGCCUGGCCAGCAGACCGCACUGCGGACCACUGUGCUUUCCGCAACCUGCUGCUGGUACGGCCCCUGGGCCCCCAGGCCAGCAUUCGGCUCUGGAAACAACUGCAAGACCCAAGGCUCCAGUGCUGACUCUCAUUGGGGAGGGCGGAGGUGCUGACCUGGCCUGGGCCUCUGGGGCCGGCCCCUGGCUCAGCCCCUCCUUCCAGGUCUUGAUGGGAGGGAGGAGGGCCCAGAAGCUGGACAACUUAAGCCACUCCUUGGCCUCCCCCAGCCAGGGGCCUGGGCAGGAAAGAUGGGGUGGUGGACUGUUUUUGCCUACUUUUUGUUUUUGAAAAACAUGCACUCCCCACUCUGA